AGCCCCGCCCCGAAGUUUGAGGGGUGUGGACGGUUUGUGACCCCCUUAGCCGACCCUACUCCUCACUGGCCGGGACAACUGGUCUUAUCACGGAGGCUGGGGCCAGGCAGCCCUUCGGUUCGGGUGGGCCCAUGGACCCCAGUCCAACGCCGAGGGAAUAGGACCAUCCAAAAGCGGAACCUUCGCCUCAGAAAAAGGGUGCGGGACCCCUCCUCACCGUGCGGUCACGGUACGGACAGGGUAGAUCACAGGCUGAGGGACAGAGCAAAGACCCCUGAGGCCGGACACCUGGGGUCCUGCCGGGCCCCUCCCCACGAGAGUUCCCUGUGUCUGUGCCAAUCGUUUUCGUCUUUCUUUGCCGCAGUUUCUUUUCCUGUAAAUCAUGGUUAAUAACAUUAACCUUCUUACCAUCAGGGGUUAGUUGUGGUUGUGAUAAAUAAUUACUACCGUUAUUAAGCAAUUGCAAUUUGCAGUGUGCCAGGCACUGUGCCAAGUAUUUUGCUUCGAUGAUUUCACGUCAUCUUCAAAACAACCUCAUGAGAUAAUUCUUUGAGCAACUACUGGGGCAUUAUAUUGGACACUUCAGUACCAAGAGAAAUACAUACGAUCCUUGUCUACCAGGAGUCUAAUAGAAAGAUGGACAGCGUGGACCCUGCCAGCAGCCAGGCCAUGGAGCUCUCUGAUGUCACCCUCAUUGAGGGUGUGGGUAAUGAGGUGAUGGUGGUGGCAGGUGUGGUGGUGCUGAUUCUAGCCUUGGUCCUAGCUUGGCUCUCUACCUACGUAGCAGACAGCGGUAGCAACCAGCUCCUGGGCGCUAUUGUGUCAGCAGGCGACACAUCCGUCCUCCACCUGGGGCAUGUGGACCACCUGGUGGCAGGCCAAGGCAACCCCGAGCCAACUGAACUCCCCCAUCCAUCAGAGGGUAAUGAUGAGAAGGCUGAAGAGGCGGGUGAAGGUCGGGGAGACUCCACUGGGGAGGCUGGAGCUGGGGGUGGUGUUGAGCCCAGCCUUGAGCAUCUCCUUGACAUCCAAGGCCUGCCCAAAAGACAAGCAGGUGCAGGCAGCAGCAGUCCAGAGGCCCCCCUGAGAUCUGAGGAUAGCACCUGCCUCCCUCCCAGCCCUGGCCUCAUCACUGUGCGGCUCAAAUUCCUCAAUGAUACCGAGGAGCUGGCUGUGGCUAGGCCAGAGGAUACCGUGGGUGCCCUGAAGAGCAAAUACUUCCCUGGACAAGAAAGCCAGAUGAAACUGAUCUACCAGGGCCGCCUGCUACAAGACCCAGCCCGCACACUGCGUUCUCUGAACAUUACCGACAACUGUGUGAUUCACUGCCACCGCUCACCCCCAGGGUCAGCUGUUCCAGGCCCCUCAGCCUCCUUGGCCCCCUCGGCCACUGAGCCACCCAGCCUUGGUGUCAAUGUGGGCAGCCUCAUGGUGCCUGUCUUUGUGGUGCUGUUGGGUGUGGUCUGGUACUUCCGAAUCAAUUACCGCCAAUUCUUCACAGCACCUGCCACUGUCUCCCUGGUGGGAGUCACCGUCUUCUUCAGCUUCCUAGUAUUUGGGAUGUAUGGACGAUAAGGACAUAGGAAGAAAAUGAAAGGCAUGGUCUUUCUCCUUUACGGCCUCCCCACUUUUCCUGGCCAGAGCUGGGCCCAAGGGCCGGGGAGGGAGGGGUGGAAAGGAUGUGAUGGAAAUCUCCUCCAUAGGACACAGGAGGCAAGUAUGCGGCCUCCCCUUCUCAUCCACAGGAGUACAGAUGUCCCUCCCGUGCGAGCACAACUCAGGUAGAAAUGAGGAUGUCAUCUUCCUUCACUUUUAGGGUCCUCUGAAGGAGUUCAAAGCUGCUGGCCAAGCUCAGUGGGGAGCCUGGGCUCUGAGAUUCCCUCCCACCUGUGGUUCUGACUCUUCCCAGUGUCCUGCAUGUCUGCCCCCAGCACCCAGGGCUGCCUGCAAGGGCAGCUCAGCAUGGCCCCAGCACAACUCCGUAGGGAGCCUGGAGUAUCCUUCCAUUUCUCAGCCAAAUACUCAUCUUUUGAGACUGAAAUCACACUGGCGGGAAUGAAGAUUGUGCCAGCCUUCUCUUAUGGGCACCUAGCCGCCUUCACCUUCUUCCUCUACCCCUUAGCAGGAAUAGGGUGUCCUCCCUUCUUUCAAAGCACUUUGCUUGCAUUUUAUUUUAUUUUUUUAAGAGUCCUUCAUAGAGCUCAGUCAGGAAGGGGAUGGGGCACCAAGCCAAGCCCCCAGCAUUGGGAGCGGCCAGGCCACAGCUGCUGCUCCCGUAGUCCUCAGGCUGUAAGCAAGAGACAGCACUGGCCCUUGGCCAGCGUCCUACCCUGCCCAACUCCAAGGACUGGGUAUGGAUUGCUGGGCCCUAGGCUCUUGCUUCUGGGGCUAUUGGAGGGUCAGUGUCUGUGACUGAAUAAAGUUCCAUUUUGUGGUCCUGCAGCCUCUUUCUGUGACAGAGAAUGGCUUUGCGCUGCCCCCAGGAAAAUGGUAAUGAGAGUAGGUAGGCCGGGGCUACCAACGGGAGAUGCAGUUUAUUUACACCAGCAGCCAUGGGGGCAGAGGGAAUACACAGCGUUUACAAAGUUAGCUACCUGUACAGAAUGGAUUACAUAUGCAAAAAUAAAAAUCUCAAGACCA